GUCACCGCUUUCGCUUCUGCUUGAGUAGUCAAGUGAAAAAAUGAGCUUCAUCUGUGGAUUGCAGUCUGCUGCUAGAAACCAUGUUUUCUUCCGAUUUAAUUCACUGUCUAACUGGAGAAAAUGUAACACAUUAGCAUCCACCUCACGGGGCUGUCAUCAAGUACAAGUUAACCAUAUAGUAAAUAAGUAUCAGGGACUGGGAGUAAAUCAGUGUGACAGGUGGAGUUUUCUGCCUGGAAACUUUCAUUUUUAUAGUACUUUUAACAACAAAAGAACAGGAGGCCUCUCAAGUACCAAAAGUAAGGAAAUUUGGAGGAUUACCAGCAAAUGUACUGUAUGGAAUGAUGCUUUUUCAAGACAGCUGCUAAUAAAAGAAGUUACAGCAGUCCCUAGUCUGUCAGUAUUGCAUCCUCUAAGCCCUGCUUCCAUAAGAGCUAUUAGGAAUUUCCAUACUUCUCCACGGUUUCAAGCUGCUCCGGUUCCUCUCUUGUUGAUGAUUCUUAAACCAGUACAGAAGUUAUUUGCAAUCAUUGUAGGCAGGGGCAUAAGGAAAUGGUGGCAGGCACUUCCUCCUAACAAGAAGGAAGUAGUUAAAGAAAAUAUAAGGAAGAAUAAAUGGAAGCUAUUCCUUGGUUUGAGUAGUUUUGGAUUGCUCUUUGUGGUGUUUUAUUUUACUCACCUGGAAGUAAGUCCAAUCACAGGAAGGAGCAAGCUACUAUUAUUGGGGAAAGAACAGUUCAGACUUUUAUCGGAACUGGAAUAUGAAGCAUGGAUGGAAGAAUUUAAAAAUGAUAUGCUAACUGAGAAAGAUGCCCGAUACCUGGCUGUUAAAGAAGUGCUUUGUCAUCUAAUUGAAUGCAAUAAAGAUGUUCCAGGGAUCUCUCAGAUCAAUUGGGUUAUUCAUGUGGUUGAUUCCCCAAUUAUUAAUGCCUUCGUGCUUCCAAAUGGACAAAUGUUUGUUUUCACUGGAUUUUUAAAUAGUGUAACCGAUAUUCAUCAACUUUCUUUCCUUCUGGGCCAUGAAAUAGCACAUGCAGUACUUGGGCAUGCUGCAGAAAAGGCUGGCAUGGUUCAUUUGUUGGAUUUCCUAGGUAUGAUUUUCCUCACAAUGAUUUGGGCCAUUUGUCCUCGAGAUAGCUUGGCACUUUUGUGCCAGUGGAUACAGUCUAAAUUGCAGGAGUAUAUGUUUAAUAGACCAUACAGCAGAAAAUUGGAGGCCGAAGCUGACAAAAUUGGACUACUGCUUGCUGCAAAGGCUUGUGCAGACAUAAGAGCCAGUUCAGUGUUUUGGCAGCAAAUGGAGUUCGUUGAUAGCCUGCAUGGCCAACCCAAGAUGCCAGAAUGGUUAUCUACACACCCUUCUCAUGGCAAUCGAGUUGAGUACUUGGAUAGACUUAUACCUCAGGCUCUCAAAAUUAGAGAGAUGUGUAAUUGUCCACCACUGUCUAAUCCAGACCCUCGAUUACUAUUCAAACUCAGCACGAAGCAUUUUCUUGAAGAAUCAGAGAAAGAAGACCUAAAUAUCACGAAGAAACAGAAAAUGGAUACUCUUCCUAUUCAAAAACAGGAGCAAAUACCAUUAACAUACAUAGUUGAGAAAAGAACGGGCAGUUGAAUUAAAAUUUAUGAGACACAAGAUAUAUGAAGAAUGUUGCAGUCCUUAUCAUUUUAUGUUACUUUUUAAAAAAUGAUGUUUGAAGUGAAAAAAAAAAGGAUAUUCAGGGUCAAAUCAUGUACAUUACAGAUAUUAUCUAAAUUCUUCUAGAAUUUAUUUUUCAUGAAAUAUUGAUGUAUUUUAAUCUAUGUUAAAAUAUCUUCAAUGAGGAAAAUGUCACAGAAUAAAUUUAUAUUACACAUUUUA